UUUUUUUUUUUUUUUUUUUUUUUUUUGAGACGGAGUCUCGCACUGUUGCUCGGGCUGGAGUGCAAUGGCAUGAUCUCGGCUCACUGCAACCUCUGCCUCCCAGGUUCAAGCGAUUCUCCUGCCUCCUAAGUAGCUGGGAUUACAGGUGCCUGCUACAAUGCCCAGCUAAUUUUUUGUAUUUUUAGUACAGAUGGGGUUUCACUAUGUUGGCCAGGCUGGUCUCAAACUCCUGACGUUGUGAUCCACCUGCCUUGGCCUCUCAAAGUGCUGAGAUUACAGGCAUGAGCUACUGUGCCUGGCUGUAAUUGCUUUUAAUUUUGAAGGAUUUAAAAGAUUAUUAUUAUCUAUUUGUCUCUGAACUAUUUCUUUGUAUACCUUUACUCUGGUCUUCUUGGAACCUAAAAGAAAGCCUCAGUCUUGCAGAGUAUAAUGCCUGAAACAUAACAUCAAUAGAUAAGUAUUUGUUGACUCAAUAAAUGGGGAAUAAGUGAAUGGCUUCCAUGCUCCUGGUAGGCAAAAAAAAUGCAAACUAUUUAGUUAUGUGAGUUGUCUAUAUUAGUCGUGCAAAACUAUCCUGGGUUUCUAGGCAGCAUAUCUGAGAAUGUUUUUUAAUAUCUGGGGGUAGAUUAAUCUACUCCUCCCUUAAAUAACAAGUCGAUCCAUUGAGAAGAAAGUGCUAUGGUGUACUCAGGCAGAAUUUAAAAGAACAUGAGCAUUACAUGAAGCAGGAAGUUAAUUUGCCUGCUGGAGUUGAUGAGGAAGUAACACAGGGAAUUAUUAUUCAUCUCUUUAGGACUGCCAGGGUGAAAAGUUUUCCCUCUUAUUACCUAAUGAGGCUCUGCCAACUGGGUACCCCAUAAGCUCCUACUGUCUGAAAAGCAGUGCCAAAUCAGGACUUUUGUUGGGAAAACUGACUCUGUGCCCAUGCGGGUGCAAAAGUCUGUCUGCAUGCUCUGGGCAGUGUGUGCUGAAUGACAAGGUGAGUCUAAAGGAGACAAAGUGACUCCUUCUACCUAGGUUAGAUUAGACGACGGCAAGGGCAGAUAAAGUUAUCUGGGAAACUCCAUGUACCAGGCUCUGGAAUCAGAUCUGUUGGAUUCUGCCUUCAGAGUAGAAUGUCUGACUGGCCUUUCUAUUGCCCUUAUCAAUGAAGACUGUUUAAAGCUGAAUUGACUGAGCAGUGUUUUUUUGUUUUGUUUUUGUUUUUGUUUUUUUUUGUAGAAGGCUGUCGCAGAGUAAAAUAAUAUCAUGAAAUGACUUCAUAAUUAGCUACUUUAGAUUCAUUUGUGGGAAAAAAAGUCAAAGUCAAAACUUUACUUCCUUUUCUUUUCCUUCCCAAAACACCUACAUCACCAUGCCCUAUUUUCUAAUUUUUUUUUUUUGCCAAAGUUAUUGACUAAUAAGAUCAUGGUAUCUUACUGGCAGAGUAAGUGGAUUAUUUUAAUUCCCAUUGGACUUCUUUUCCAAGUGACUUCCUCAGCAAUAAGGAAAGAGUUCCCACAUCUGAGCUCUAAAAGUGGUUAAUGGAUGUGUCUUUCUCUACAAAUUUAGUGUCUUAAAGGCACACAACAUACUUACUUAAAGGAAGCUCUCCUGUAGUUCUACUGUGAUUUUCAUGUCCAUGCCCAUGGGAAAGAGCCUCUGUCUUCAAUCUUACAUAGUUACUCUGGGUCUCAUAACCAAAUUAAGAGCAGAAGAAAAUACUGAGUGGUAAAUUAAAUCAGCUUUCCCAGAGGUUAGAAACACUUCUCAGCUACCUCUGUAUUCAUACAUCUAUUUUCCAAUCUGUUCAAUUCAGCUGUCACAAUUUCACCCCAUUUACCCCUUGCUAACACUUGAAAUGCUGCCUUUAAUUAAUUCUCCACACUCAGAACUUUGAGCAAUGCCAAGUUAGUUAAUUAUCCAAGUGUAUUGCUUUAAGCAUUUCCUAGAUGCGAAUUAUAAAAAUUCUUGGUGAGUGCCAGCAUCAUAUCUUCAAAGACUUGAGCUUCCUUGCCCUCCACAGAGCUGUGCUGGAUACGAAAUGAGCAGAUGGCACAGAACAGUAUCUAGAUUAAAUUUUCUCUCUCAACUAUGAUAUAGGUAUCCAGAAACAUCCUCCUUUACUUUACUGAUGAAGUGGAAAGGUUGAAAGGAAAGGUGUAACCAGCUUUUGAAUAAGUUGGACUAGAAUUAUUAUUGUAUAACUUCUCUAAGAUCUCUAGGGGCUUAUAGCUUUGUGCUAGGUGUUACCAGUUGAAAUGAGAUAAGAUUAUCAUGGAUGCCAAAUUUUACUGUUGUAGUAGAAAUUUGUUUUACAAAACGUCUCUCAUGAGAAAAGAAAGGAAAGCAAUAACAUUUAUUUAUUUUCUUUUUCUCUGCAGGCAUUCUAAUAUAUGCAUUCUUCAUAACAACUGUGUGAAACAUAUUAAUAUCCUCAUUGUUAACGAUGAAGAAACUAAAUCUCAGGAAGAAAAACUAAGUGAAGACAAAAGAAGGAUUUGAACUGAGGUUUGUCAGACUCUCGGGACCAUGCUGUUGAAACCACUAAACCACGCUGCCUCUGGGUCACUUGAUUAUUCUGGGAGAUUCUGGGAGUCUUUUCUCCAACACUCCAGUGGCAUCUGACUAUGUGAGCUGAUAAGAUCUAUAGAUCUGUGAGUUGGCAGAGCUGUGAAAAGUUUCUCCCUUCUUAGGACAUAAGCAGGAAAUCUUGAUACAGGAAUCAAUAAGGGGAAAGAGAAAAUGUUUAUUAGAACAAAUUUAUUAUAUUUGGGUGAACAAAACACUUAUUUUACAGUAGACUAAACUCCAGGAUAUGGAAUAUUUCUCAAUUUCUUUAACUUGCUAUUGUUGAAUAUAAUUUUGGCUAUAGUCACUUUGAGUGAUGGUUCCAAACAAGGCAGAAUUUGGCCUCUAGAAACAGAGAGAAAUAUCCAGAGAAAAUAUGGAACGUUCACUGGCCUCAGAGUAAAAAGUUCCAAAUUGAAGUCCUAUCUUUGGUGACAAUUAAUGGAAUGAAGUUGGGUUAGUCAUCAGACUUUUAAAAACCUUCGUUGCUGAAUCUGCAGAAUGGGCACAUUAGAAAUGUCAAUCAUAUUGCUGCCAUGCAAACAGACUCCUCUAUUUGGUGCUAUUUCAACCAAGUAACUUUCCUGCCUACAGCAACAGAAAACUGGUUCAGGGUGAACACCUGUCAUAAGGUGAACUAGCUAACUUUGAGGAGGUUUAUCAUAAAAAGAUGAACUGGAUUUGAAAUAGGAAACAGAGUGAAACAUGAGGUAGAAUCAGGACCAAGAGAAGUCUUGGUGAGCCGAAGUUAGGAUCAUUUCAAUCAAGUAACAGUGAGGUUGAGAAAAGAUUUAUAGACUCAAAGACAAGACUAAGUCAGUUAUUACAUUAGCAUAGUCAUUGAGACCAUAGGUUUUGGAGUGAAAUGGAUGUAGAUUCUUAUUAGCUGUGUGAUCUUCAGCAAUUUACUUAACAUCUCUAAGGUUCUGGUUUCUUGUCAGUAAAAUGAAGAUAAUAGUAAAUAAAUAGUAAAAUGGAGAUAAUUUUCAUUAUAAGAUUGUUGUGAGGAUUUUAAUUAAUACAUGAUAAACCCGUAGAACAGUGGCUGGCAUUUUGCUAAUUCUACAUCAGUGAUAUGGUUUAGCUGUGUCCCCACCCAAAUCUCAUCUUAAAUUCCCACAUGUUGUGGGAGGGACCCAGUGGGAGGUAAUUGAGUCAUGGGUGCAUGUCUUUCCCAUGCUGUUCUCAUGGCAGUUAGUCUCAUGAAAUCUGAUGGUUUUAUAAAGAGGAGUUCCCCUGCACAAGUGCUCUCUCUUUGCCUGGUGCCAUCCAUGUAAGACGUGACUUGCCCCUCUUUGCCUUCUGCAUGAUUGUGAGGCUUCCCCAGCCAUGUGGAACUGUAAGCCCAUUAAACCUCUUUCUUUUGUAAAUUGUGCAGUCUCAGGUAUGUCUUCAUCAGCAGCAUGAAAAUAGACUAAUACAGUAAAUUGGUAUCAGUAGAAUGGGGUGCUGUGGAAAAGAUACCUGAAAAUGUGGAAGCAACAUUGGAACUGGGUAACAGGCAGAGGUUGGAACAGUUUGGAGGAUUCAGAAGAAGAGAGGAAAAUGUGGGAAAGUUUGGAACUUCCUAGAGACUUGUUGAAUGGCUUUGACAAAAAUGCUGAUAGUGAUAUGAACAAUAAGGUCCAGGCUGAGGUGGUCUCAGAUGGAGAUGAGGAACUUGUUGGGAACUGGAGCAAAGGUGACUCUUUUCAUGCUUUAGCAAAGAGACUGGUGGCAUUUUGCCCCUGCCCUAGAGAUCUGUGGAACUUUGAACUUGAGAGAGAUGAUUUAGGUUAUCUGGUGGAAGAAGUUUCUAACCAGCAAAGCAUUCAAGAGGUGACUUGGGUGCUGUUAAAGGCAUUCAGUUUUUUAAAGGGAGCAGAGCAUAGAAGUUUGGAAAAUUUGCAGCCUGACAAUGUGAUAGAAAAGAAAAUCUCAUUUUCUGAGAAGAAAUUCAAGCCGGCUGCAGAAAUUUGCAUAAGUAACAAGGAGCCGAAAGUUAAUCCCCGAGACAAUGAGGAAAAUGUCUCCAGGGCAUGUCUAAGGUCUUCACAGCAGCCCCUUUUGUCACAGGCACAGAGACCUAGGAGGAAAAUAUGGUUUAGUGGACUGGGCCCCAGCUGUGUGCAGCCUAGGAACUUGGUGCCCUGUGUCCCAGCUGCUCUAGCCAUGGCUGAAACGGGUCAAUGUAGAGCACGGGCCAUGGCUUCAGAGGGUGCAAGCCUCAAGCCUUUGCAGCUGCCACUUGGUAUUGAGACUGCCAGUACACAGAAGUCAAGAAUUGGGGUUUGGGAACCUCUACCUAGAUUUCAGAAGAUGUAUGGAAACACCUGGGUGUCCAGGCAGAAGUUUGCUGCAGGAGUGGGGCUUUCAUGGAGAACCUCUGCUAGGGCAAUGCAGAAGGGAAAUGUUGGGUUGGAGCCACCACACAGAGUCCCUACCGGGGCACCACCUAGUGGAGCUGUGAGAAAAGGGUCACCAUCCUCCAGACCCCAGAAUGGUAGACUCACUGAUAGCUUGCACUGGCACCUGGAAAAGUCACAGAUACUCAAUACCAGUCCAUGAAAGCAGCUGGGAGGGAGGCUGUACCCUGCAAAGCCACAGAGGCAGAGCUGUCCAAGAUCAUGGGAACCUACCUCUUGCAUCAGCGUGACCUGGAUGUGAGACAUGGAGUCAAAGGAGAUUAUUUUGGAACUUUAAGAUUUGAUUGCCCUGCUGGAUUUCAGACUUGCAUGGGGCCUGUAGCCCCUUUGUUUUGGCCAAUUUCUCCCAUUUGGGAUGGCUGUAUUUACCCAAUGCUGUACCCCCAUUGUAUCUAGGAAGUAACGAACCUGCUUUUGAUUUUACAGGCUCAUAGGCCUAAGGGACUUGCCUUUUUUCAGAUGAGACUUUGGACUGUAGACCUUUUAGUUAAUACUGAAAUGAGUUAAGACUUUGGGGGACUGUUGGGAAGGCAUGAUUGGUUUGAAAUGUGAGGACAUGAAAUUUGGGAGGGGCCAAGGGUGGAAUGAUAUGGUUUGGCUGUGUCUGCACCCAAAUUUCAUCUUGAAUUCCCACGUGUUGUGGGAGGGACCGAGUGGGAGGUAAUUGAAUCAUGGGGGCGGGUCUUUCCCAUGCUGUUCUCAAUUAUAGUAAAUAAGUCUCACAAGAUCUGAUGGUUAUUAUAAGGGGGAGUUCUCCUAUACGAGUUCUCUCUCUUUGCUGCCAUCCAUGUAAGAUGUGACUUGCUCCUCCUUGCCUUCUGCCAUGAUUGUGAGGCUUCCCCAGCCACGUGGAACUGUAAGUCCAAUUAAACCUCUUUCUUUUGUAAAUUGCCCCGUCUUGGGUAUGUCUUUAUCAGCAGCAUGAAAAUGGACUAAUACAAUCAGUGUUUGACUUAUUACCUGAGAGGUAUCAUACUAAGUGUUUAUGUGAUUUAUGUCAGUGAAUCUUUCAACAACUUUAUGAGGAUUAUUUUAUUAAUAUCUCCACUUUGUGGAAGAAUAAACUGAGGCACAUACAGGUUUAUUAACAUCUUCCUGUCACACAGGUAGUAGGUGGCAAAGCUUGCAUUUGAAGUGGGGCUUUAUGGCUUCAGAGUCUGCUUGUUCACCAUUACCUUCCACUGCUUCUCUAUAAUUGAUGAGUAGCAGCAAGAAGAAUGUAGAGCAGGCAAAUAGAAAGUAGCUGAGCCCUAGAAGUGGCUGAUAACUUGUGUAAGAAGAGCAAAAUCAGGCUGUGGGGAUUUAUGGCUGCCCUGGGUUCAUUGCAGGUCUUGGGAAGCCUGGCCAUGCCUAAUCCUUUUUUUUUUUCGGAUCCCACAAGAUCCUAUGUGUCCUUGCAGGAAGUUUCCCGUUUCAGGAGAAGGCUCCAGUGAGCCUCUGUUCCAAGCAUGACACUGAGCCACUGGGUGUCAACCCUUGCUCUAUCUUGAAGAAACAAGGUUUGUCAAAGAUUUUUGUUCCAUGGAAACAGGGAUUGGUUUGGUUUGGUCACCAUCAUCCACCUAACAUUUAGCAUAGCACAUAGUAGGGGUUCCUGAAAUAACUUUUUGAAAGAAUGAGUAAAAAACUGGAGUAAAACAAAUGUAAAGCACUGCUUUCUUCUAAUUACUGAUAUAACUAUUUCUUUCAAUGACUAAUUCCUCAUGCACUAGUCUACAUAGUUAUAGAAAAAUGACCUUUUGUUGAAAAACAGAAGGAAUUGUACAAUAGUUAUAAAAUAAGUGUUUCAAAUUCCUAUUACUUGAAGGACUGAGGGAGCAAAAAGAUAUUUCAGGUUAUUAAUCUAUAUUUAUCAUGUCAACAAUUUAUCAGGCAGAAUGCCUAACAAUAAAAGCCCCAUUAUGGCUUCAUUUAACAUGAAAUACCGUGUUAUUAACUUACAAUAUUAUGUGUAUUUCACCCUGAUCAUAGACAUUUCAAAGAGCUCACAGUCUCUUUCCAUCUCUGCAGGUAGUUAAAAAAAGAUUUAACUUCUAUCGCUAUAGCAAACCAUAUUCUAGUGAAUACUGACCUUCUUGAGGGUCAUAUGCCUAUACCCUCUGAACUAAAAUUUGCUAAUGAUAUUUCACAAAUCUCCAGAAAUAGAUGCUUUAAUUCUGUCCAAUGUUACAUUCUCUUCAAACAAUGCCUCUCUUUUUCUUGCUGAAAAUUCAUAGCAAGACCAGCGGUCGAUGAAGCCAAACACUUCCCAGGCUUCCCCUUGAUCCUCCUGCAUCAAAUGCUUAAAAUUUAAUGCUGGAGCUUAUAGCGCCAUGAGCUCCAGAGAUAGAAGUAAAUGAAAAGUCAACCUUUCAGGCUGUAUUUCUGCUCAAGCUUUUGUGUUUGUGGUUCCCCCCACCAUGGCAGCUGAAACAGUUUGCUAUCAGAACACUCUACUGUCAGAGGAACUUUGUGAUCAACACGACGCAGAGAUUGGAAAAUGUCACUAUUAGGGAAUUACAGUAACCAGGGCUCUUUCUGACCAGGUCCAUUUGUGCUUGCAGAAUUUUGUCAACACAGCAGGAGCCUGGGGAGUCAGGCCACUUGUAGUAGCACGUGGGAGUAUAUGCUUGCUUUUUCUCAGGGAAAAUUCAGAAGAUUAGAAGGCUUAGCUGCUCUGAGUAUCUCUGAGCCUCUGUAUCCUCAGAGGAUAGUGCUUUAAGGAGGAAGUGUGGUGGGCAUCAUCUGACAUCUGCAAUGGCCAUGAUAGGUUACCAUCGUAAUCUGUUUUUGUGUCUGUCUUGAUAAAAACUAGAAAUAUAAAUUUAUGUGUACCAUUUCUACAGUAGAUUUAUCCUAGCAUAAUUCAGACACUUACAACUUCUUUCUAGGAGACAGAAACUUUGGGGAGAGGAUGUGUGACAAGCAAGAACAUUGUUACAUGAUAUGGUCACAGGGCUCCUGGACUCCUUUUCUGCACACUCUGCUACACUGCUAUGGAGGCCACACUGUCUUAUCUUAAGACUUUUCUUCCCUUUACUUUCCCUUCUAGGAAUCCCACUCAUUUUGCCCACAGGCCUUGGUAUUCCCUCAAAAUAGUGUUUCUUGUAACAGCCACAGACUCAAAAAAUCAUUCAAUUUACCUUACCCUGAAUACCACACAGGCCUCUGAGACAGCCUGGACAAGGCCCUAGUGAUGUUUACCAAGUCUCCCUCUGUCAGGUCACUGGAUUGCAUAUUUAUUGGCCAGUGUACACACAGCACAGUGAUGAAAAAUGAUACCCCACAGCCAUAUUGAAGCAAUAUUCCAAGGUGUGUGAGGCCGUCAACUCAAAACCCUUUGAGAGAUUACCCCAUCCCCAGCCAUAUGUUUGGUACUACAGGUACGUUUUUCUGCCUUUACCACUUUGGGAAUUUUUUUGACAAGGGGUCUCCGAUGACUGCCUUGUUGCUGUGCAGGGAGGAGAGAAGUGAGGCUCAGGUUUCAACUGAGGUGUUAAUUAUACCAGUGACAGACUUGCUUUAUUAGGGCUUAAUUGACAUCUUUGUCUCAAGCUUGAGAAAUCUAAACAAAGAAUAUUUAAACUUUGGCUUUAGUUUUGCCUCGACCAAAAAUAAUUAUUAUUCCUAUAAGUUGUAUAGUGAUGUAUUAGGGGUCAAAUGGAAAUAAAAUUUGAGGCAAAUCCAAUGUCAUUUAGAGUUACUUGCUUUGCCACAGCCAUGAUCCUUACAGCACGAAAUAAGCCUCAGAUCAGAGGGGUUUCUCUAGAGCAAAGACAUAGGUGUGCAGGUGUAGAACACGUUUAAACAAAGCCCCCACCCUUGUUGAAAGAAUGUGCUAUUCCAUUAGAGGUUUUAUGAAUGUGAGUAUCAUUUGAAUCUUUCUAAAUGAAUGAGCCUGAUUUUCCUAACCAUUAACCGUAGAGUAGUUUUAAUGGCUCUACUCCAUGAAAUACAUGCUGACAGUGAAACUGCCUUUAUAAGGUGUUCUAUGACUUUCAAUGCUAUCGUUCUGUAGUCAAAUGUAUUUUUAUUAUAGAUAUUAACAGUUGGUUAGACUUUCUUUACCUGCCCAUUAUGUUCAUAAAUCAGUGCAUCUGUAAUAGUUAAGAAAGAAGAACUUGUUAAAGCUUAUGUUUAUUCUUCCACAUAAUAAUCUUAGGAGCUAGAUAGGUGCUUAUUCAUUACCCAUUAAUGUUGGAUUUCUCCAGAAUAAAUAGAAGACUAAAUCUAUCCUAUGAGCCUUGGGUAGAUGCAGAGUUGGGAUUUAUCAGAGAAAUAUUUAAAUAGUUCAUAAGGGCAAGUUCAUCCCCUCAGCAGGCAUCUACUAAGGUCUGUUGUUGACCAGACUACACACUAGGCUGGGGGUCUCACCAACAUGAGGAGGAUAAGUCUGACCCUUGAAGAACUUGCUUUCUCAUAGCUGAAGGAAGGUUGUGGACGCCUGGUCUGAAAUUGACAUUUGGAAGCCUGGAGAGGAUCAAUGUCCUCCCCUUUUAACCCCAGCCUACAGGAAAAGGAUUGUGGGGAGAGGAAUCUUCCUGGUAGAAGACAGGGAGGGAUGACCUGUUGGUGGUAAGACAGAUUCAGUUAAGGGGAGGGAAGUAAAAAAUGAAGCAUGGGAUAGGGAUAAAUGUGAUGGAGGUAAGAGAUCUUUGUAGAAAACUAAUAAAGCCAGUGGAAAAAAGAAAAACAAGAGAUAUUUUCCCUUCCUUCUAGGAGGAAUGGAGGAAAUAAAUAUUCAUUGGGUUUCUGCUAUGAGCCAUACAGUGUGCUAGGUGUUUCACAGGUGUUCCAUUUUUUUCUUAAAACAGCCCUGUAAGUUGAUGUUAUGUCCAUUUUAUAGGUGGGAGAAUGAAGUGAGCAAGGUUAAAUAUCUACUAAAAUUCACAUUCCAAUGCAUGGUAAAAGUGAUGUUCAAACACAGGUGUGUUCAUCUCCAAACACACUCUGUUUACGUGACAGAUGCCAAGACCUCAACUGCAAAUGGACAAACAUGUUCAUUUAUUAAUUCAACAAAUGUUGAGCCCUAUUGUCUGCCAGACAGUCGAGGAUAUUUCUCUCUCACUCCUUACUUUUGGGCUUUCAUGCGUUUCUCCUCUCCUUGCCUCUAAGCCUUAUACCCUUUUAAGCUUUUUUUAAUUUGUCACUUGUGAAGAAUUGAUGAUUUUGUAUCCCAGGUCUGCUGUUCAGGAAAUUAAAUUGUUUUGUUACUUUGAGCCUGUGAGUUCUCUUCUGUAAGGUGAAGGAUAGUAAGAAUCUUUCUUUCAUAAUGUUGGGUAGUUUAAAUGAGGUAAUGUAUGCAAAAGAGCCCAGUGCCUGACAGAUGGCAGGUGCUCAACAUGUGUGUUCAUUAAGGUAGUCAACCAAAGAUUCUCCCACCGAAGCAGAAAGUGGUACAGAGAAUAUCUCCUUGGAGAACAAUAACUCUGCUGAUGGUGAUGAUGGUGAAUAAUGAUACAGAAAAUCCUUAAAGACAGAGCACAAGUAGGCUUCCUAAAUAUAUAUUUUGUAUGGCAUACUAAGCUUAACAGUAGCUCCUAAGAUUAUUAUGUGGAAGAAUAUAAGUAAGCUUUAACACAUUCUUCUUUCUUAUUUAUAGUGGAUGCACUGAUUUAUGAACAUCAUGGGUAGAUAAAGAAAAUCUAACCAACUGCUAAUAUCUAUAAUAAAAAAUGUUUACGGGGGCCAGGCGUGGUGGCUAAUGCCUGUAAUCCCAGCACUUUGGGAGGCUGAGGCGGGCAGAUCAUGAGGUCAGGAGAUCGAGACCAUCCUGGCUAACAUGGUGAAACUCCGUCUCUACUCAAAAAUACAAAAAAAUUAGCCAGGUGUGGUGGCAGGUGCCUGUAGUCCCAGCUACUCAGGAGGCUGAGGUAGGGGAAUGGUGUGAACCCAGGAGGCAGAGCUUACAGUGAGCUGAGAUCGCACCAUUGCACUCCAGCCUGGGCGACAGAGCAAGACUCUGUCUGAAAAAAAAAAGAAAAAAAUGUUUACGAAGCAGAAGCAGCAGCAGAAGGAAAAAAAAAAUCACUUGCUGACAUUUCAAAUCA